GCUCUCCCCAGCGCCUGCCGCCGACGCCGCCGCCUCCUCCCGCCGCGCGGACCGUGGAGCGGGGUCGCAGCCGCCUGCCCGCCCUGCGGUGGGCCAGGAUGUCGGGCUUCCUGGAGGAGCUGCUCGGCGAGAAGCUGGUGACGGGCGGCGGCGAGGAGGUGGACGUGCACUCGCUGGGCGCCCGCGGCAUCUCGCUGCUGGGUCUCUACUUCGGCUGCAGCCUCAGCGCCCCCUGCGCGCAGCUCAGCGCCAGCCUGGCCGCCUUCUACGGGCGCCUGCGGGGGGACGCGGCGGCCGGGCCGGGGCCGGGAGCGGGGGCCGGGGCGGCGGCGGAGCCCGAGCCGCGGCGGCGCCUGGAGAUCGUCUUCGUGUCCUCGGACCAGGACCAGCGGCAGUGGCAGGACUUCGUGCGGGACAUGCCGUGGCUGGCGCUGCCCUACAAGGAGAAGCACAGGAAGGUGCAUUUUUUGUUUUUGUUUUUGAGACGGAGUCUUGCUCUGUCGCCCAGGCUGGAGUGCAGUGGCGCGAUCUCGGCUCACUGCAAGCUCCGCCUCCCGGGUUCACGCCAUUCUCCUGCCUCAGCCUCCCAAAGUGCUGGGAUUACAGGCGCCCGCCACCACGCCCGGCUGAUUUUUUGUAUUUUUAGUAGAGACGGGGUUUCACCACGUUAGCCACGAUGGUCUCGAUCUCCUGACCUCGUGAUCUGCCCUCCUCGGCCUCCCAAAGUGCUGGGAUGACAGGCGUGAGCCACCGCGCCCGGCCCAGCAUUUUAUUU